ACGCCGCCUUCGCCGCUGGCUCCGUCUGUUGGGGGGCGAACACGCCGCGGUCCUCGUCGUGGUGAGCGCAGCCACUCAGGCUGGUCCUGGGGGUGGGGCUGUAGGGGAAAGUGCUAAAGCCGCUGAGGUGCAGUGGCUCACGCCUGUAAUCCCAGCACUUUGGGAGGCCAAGGCAGGUGGAUCACCUGAGGUCGGGAGUUCAAGACCAGCCUGACCAACAUGGAGAAACCCCAUCUCUACUAGAAAUACAAAAUUAGCCAGGCAUGGUGGUGCAUGCCUGUAAUCCCAGCUACUCGGGAGGCUGAAGCAGGAGAAUCGCUUAAAUCCGGGAGGCAGAGGUUGCUGUGAGCCGAGAUCGCGCCAUUUCCAGCCUGGGCAACAAGAGGGAAACUCCGUCUCAAAAAAAAAAAAAAAAAAGAAGAGAAAAGAAAACAUAAGUUUCAGCCAGGCAUGUGAAGUAAGAACUCUGCUAGAGAGGAAAUGGCUGCUUCAUCAUCAUCCUCCUCAGCUGGUGGGGUCAGUGGAAGUUCUGUCACUGGAUCUGGUUUCAGUGUCUCAGACCUUGCCCCACCACGGAAAGCCCUUUUCACCUACCCCAAAGGAGCUGGAGAGAUGUUAGAAGAUGGCUCUGAGAGAUUCCUCUGCGAAUCUGUUUUUAGCUAUCAAGUGGCAUCCACGCUUAAACAGGUGAAACAUGAUCAGCAAGUUGCUCGGAUGGAAAAACUAGCUGGUUUGGUAGAAGAGCUGGAGGCUGACGAGUGGCGGUUUAAGCCCAUCGAGCAGCUGCUGGGAUUCACCCCCUCUUCAGGUUGAUACUGCCUGGAUGGUCACCUCUGGUGCGCAGCAAGUGCAAAGCCAGUGGGGGACUUUCUCACAGCUUACAUAGCCAUCCAGAGAUCCACAGCUACGUCACUGAAUUGUUAAUGCACAUUUGUACUUGGUUUCUCUGUAUCUAUUCACAGGCAACAAAUACUUAUAUGUGUGAUCUUUCAGGGAAUGUUUUGUUUAUUUGUUUUUAAAAGUAUUGGGAAUCAGAUUAAGACAAUCAGUUUCAGAGAACCAGGAGGUUUGGGGUUAAGAGAUACUCAAAAAUUUUCACAAGCCAAGUAGGGCAUAUAUCAGAUUUGGCCAACUGAAUGGCGUCUGUCCUGUCAUCCAUAUGGUGCCUGGAAAUAUUUACCAGUCAAGGUCAAGGUCAGCAUCUGUGGUUAAAAAUAUAGCAUUCUGACCUAAAAAAGUUAUUUUGCAGAUGAAUGUGUUUUCAACUCAGGACCUAUCCAAAUGAGGAAUUUUUAAAUAUUCUUUUUUUUUUCCUAUUUUUAGACAUCAAUUCUAUAGAUUCUGACUUUUUCUAACCUCUUAUAGACAUGCCAAAUGCUGGCAAAAAGAAGUGCUUUUUGGAUAUGGCAGCACUUGUAAAAAUAAAGCAGUAAGCAAAAUCCUUUUAAACACAGAAAUCCUGAGUUCUUCUCAUUGGUGGACUCAAGCAAUUCUGUAGCAAAUAAAUCCUUUGAAAGAGCUCCAAAUUGGUGGCAUUAUCCUUUCAAAAUCUCAGGGAUUUGGGAUGAAGUGAAGAGGUCAAAUUACUUUUUAGAAGAAGGGAAUCUAAAAACCAUCUCUCCUAAACAAAUGGUAGACUGGCUUUACUUAAGGGAUAUUUGUCUUUAUAGGAGUACAUAAAUUUAUCUUAAUGAUAUUUAAGUAGUUUUUUUUUUUUUUUGAGACGAAGUUUUGCUCUUGUUGCCCAGGCUGUAUCGCAAUGGCGCGAUCUCUGCUCACUGCAACAUCCACCUCCCAGGUUCAAGCAAUUCUCCUGCCUCAGCCUCCCAAGUAGCUGGGAUUACAGGCACCCGCCACCACACCCAGCUAAUUUUUUGUAUAUUUAGUAGAGACGGGGUUUCACCAUGUUGACCAGGCUAGUCUCGAACUUCUGACCUCAGGUGAUCCACCUGCCUCAGCCUCCCAAAUUGCUGGGAUUACAGGCGUGAGCCACCUUGCCCAGCCAAUUUUUUUUUAAAGAGACAUGGUCUUGCUAUGUUGCCCAGGUUGGUCUUGAACUCCUGGCCUCAAGAGAUCCCCCCAACCUUGGCCUCCAAAGUGCUGGGAUUACAGGCAUGAGCCACCGCGCCUGGCCUCAAGUAAGUUUUUAUACCAUGAUAGGGGAAAACCUGGAAGGCUAAGAGAUGUGCUGUUUUCCUUCAUGGGACCCCACUUUCCACAGUAAACAACUGGUAUAAUCAUUUAUUACGUUGUAUGCAAAUUUUGCCUUAGACAACAUUUGUCUGGUUCCUUAUUAAUAACUUGCAUCUGAUCUGCUUAGAGUUGCUUAAUUAUAAGUAAAUAUAAUCCCAGUAGCAUUUAGCCUUAAUCUCAAGAGUUCAAAAUGUUUAACACAUUCUACCUGACGGGAGGUGGUGACCUCAUUCAGUCGGUUAAGAGCCUGAGCCCUGUGAAGUUAAACACCUGCUCAUGGUCACAUAGCCCAGGCAGAAGAAAAUCUCGGACUUGGAAUAGAUCCCAGUUGCCUGAUAAUUCAUCUCAUUAUUGCCUCUAAAGCAAAUUGGAGACUGGGCACAGUGGCUCCCACCUUUAAUCCCAGCACCUGGGGAGGCUGAGGUGAGUGGAUCACUAGAGGUCAGGAGUUCAAGACCAGUCUGGCCGACAUGGUGAAACUCAGUCUCUAUUGAAAAUACAAAAAUUAGCUCAGUGUGGUGGCACACACUUGUAAUCCCAGCUACUCAGGAGGCUGAGGCAUGAGAAUCGCUUAAACCCAGGAGGCGGAGGUUGCAGUGAGCUGAGAUCACACCAUUGCACUCUAGUCUGGGUGACAGAGCGAGACUCUGUCUCAAAAAAAAAAAAAUAAAGCCGGGCGUGGUGGCUCACGCCUGUAAUCCCGGCACUUUGGGAGGCUGAGGCAGGCGGAUUGCCUGAGAUCGGGAGUUCGAGACCAGCCUGGCCAACAUGGUGAAACCUUGUCUCUACUAAAACUACAAAAAAAAUUAGCCAGGCGUGGUGGCGGGCGCCUGUAAUCCCAGCUACUCAGGAGGCUGAGGCAGCAGAAUCGUUUGAACCCGGGAGGCGGAGGUUGCAGUGAGUGGAGAUCGUGCCUGUGUGCUCCAGCCUGAGCAACAAGAGCGAAACUGUCUCAAAAAAAAGAAGAAAAUAAAUAAAUAAAAAUCAGAGCACAAGAAGUACCAGUCCACCAACUCACAUUUUCUAUAUUAAUAAUUCUUAACUAAAAGAAGUUCCAUAUUCGACAGCAUUUUAGUUUUUUAAUAGUACUUAUUAGCAUCAACCAUCUUGAUAAUCACCAAGGGAAAAAUUAAAAAUACCUAGACUGCAAUAAACCUUUAAAUUGGAUUUUCAGUGAGAAUUUAGAAGCAAUCACUACCUUUCUCGUUUCAUUUGUGUAACCAUGCAGCAUAGGCACUGUGUUACAUCAUCUUUACGCUUUGGUAUUUGAACUUAUUACAGAAUUUUUUCUCUAAAUUGGAUGUUUCUUUAUAUGACCUUGGAAACUGAAGUGAUCUUAGCAUUAAACAAAAAUGCUUUUUGAA